CCGCUCAGGAUUGGUCCCUGGGAGGCAAGAGGGACUCACAGGGAGCAGUUGCUGGGUGGUUGUGUGUGUUGGACCCUGGGCUACCCCCUCUCCCGAGUUCCCUGGGUUUGGUGUAGGCAUGGCCUGGUGACAAUUCCACUUUUCAUUGCCAGACCUGGGAGCAUGGCCAGGAGCUAGGGUUUCCCGCGAAGUUAGGGGGAGAUUGGGGAGAGGGAAGCCGCUUCAUGACCGAGAUGGGGUCCUGGGACUCAUCUCUAGGGGGCGUGAGGCCCUCAGACCCAGGACGAGUCCAGAAGUCUCAGCGGGCACAGGCUUUGAUUCUUGGCCCAGUCUGGCCCUCUUCCUCUGUAGGCCCGGGUCUCCAAGGAGAGUACGUUUUUCAGUUUCAGAGGGUUUUCCUGAAGGGGCAGUAACCUGUCAGAGAGAGAGUGGCCUAUGGGAGACCCGGCUCCUGAAGGUGGCCGGGAUGGUUGGAGCCCUUUCUCUUGGGUUGUCAGAGAUGGGAGUAAAGCUUCAUGGCCCAGGGAAUCUUCUGGGCAUCUCUACUCUCCCAGCCAGAGGCCCAGGAACCAACUCCUUGGCUUCUGGGUAGAGUAACCUGAACCCAGUGGCCGAGCACCUCUUAAAUGCCAGGAAGGGCACUGGGCCGUGCCCCUGGAAUGUGUGGAUGGAGGAGGAUUUGGAGGAUUCUGUCCUCAGGAGGCUCAGCCCCUGGGGGCAAGACAGGACAUAAACACACAAAGUUCCCCGAUACAGGGUUUCAAUACCAGUCCUGAACUGGUAAUAGUGGAAAGCCAAGAGGCUACACACCAUUAAUUGCUAUGUGAGUAAUGUAGGCUGCGAGAGUGCCAGGGCAGCAGAGAUCCAGUUCCAUGCAAGCAAGCAAAUGUGCUGAAAUGUUCCAGCUCCAUGCCCGCCCUUCCUUAUUACCUUGCUCCAAGGGCAGGGAGCAGCAGGGGCGCUGAGGAGGUUCUCCUGCACUCAUCCCCACCCACUCCCAGGUUUGUUUGUUUCCUGCUGGUGGAUUUCUGAAAUAACCCAUUUGGUUUCUUGGCUUGGGCUGAGCACAGGACACUCCUAGUUGCCCUGUGGCUCCUGGGGUUUGGGGUCUAGAGCCAGCCUUGUAGGAGGUUCAGAGGUAAGCAGGAGGAAGUCCUCACUUCCUUUCUGAAGAGCCUCUGUCGCGGGGGGUUGGGGUAGGUCGGGAGGCUGGCAGGCACUGGGCCAGUUUCCUAUGAGUGCAGACAGACCCCAGGUGGUGCAUGCACCCCCCUCCCUUUCCUGGCCAGUGUUGGGGGUGGGCACAGUAGGGCCCAGGUGGCUUGAGGUGGGUGGUUCCUGGCACAGCUCUGACCUCACUUCUGUGAGGCUCUGCUGUAUCUGGGGCCCUGCCCCCUCCCUCAUUGUCCCUGGCAGGUUUCUGUUUUUCUGGAGCACUUCGUGGAGGUGGCAGUGUGCUCAUGCUCGUGGCCUUGGGUGCAGUUCUGGGAGUGGGAGUUGCUGAGCUCACCCGAAGCCCUUGGCUGGCACUGUGAGAACUUGUGUGAACACACUUGCCUGCCUCCAAACAGGUGGUGCACAGACCUGGGUUACCCAGGCACCUGUGGGGGAUGCCCCGUGUGGGCAGAGACGUGAGUGCGUGUGUGUGCUCAGGUUUACAUCUGUGUGGGCAGAGACGUAGAGGAGCUGGAUACAUAUAUACUUGAGGACAGACACAGGAGGAUGGUGGGGGUGAGCAAACAACCCAGGGACACAGACAUGUGCGGGGACAGACAUACAUGAACCCAUCAGCGUGGGCCACGUAUGGGCUGCAGACACGUACAUAGAAAUACACCAUUGCUGGGAUCUGAAUCUCCCCACAUGGGAGGCAGACAUGUAAGUGGACAGACAUAUAGGUAGACCCAGCAGAGCACAGACGGGGAUGGGAACCGACAUUCCCAGACAAAAGACUCGGAGCCACAGGGAAGCCGCUCAAGUGCCUGGGCAGAAUGGAGUUGGCUGUGAGCUCCUGGGGGGCACAGACACAUAUGCUUGCCAGAGCCAGCGGACAGCAGAGGCCAGGAACCAGACACAGGUGGGUUCUGAGAGGUAGGCCGAGGCGUGCAUUGCCUGGUUAUCACUGUUUCCCUGCGUGGCACAGUGCCCGGAAGUUGUCCUGUUUGGGGUGGUGAUGGUACAGGUGCUCUGUGGUGGAGCUUAUUUCUAGACUCUCACUUUGGGGUUUGAGGACCCCAAAAAGCUCAGUCUCCUGUGUUUUACUCAGAGUCAUUUGGCCUCUCCACCUCUGCAUUACAAGGCUGUGUUUGUGCCUUAAGUGCCAGCAGGUGCUCUUUGAAUUUUGAUUCUCAUCUUCCCUGGAUCUCCAGAGGCUUCCUGAAGUGAGGCUGUGUGGCCUGGGUAGGGUGCUCCAACUGUUCCUUUCCUACCAGAAUAGGAGAGGAACUGUCUGGGGAUUCUCCUUCUGAACCCAAGCCUGCGGGUCUUUGACAGGGAUCCCCCAGGUGAGAGAGAGAGCACACAUGUAGCUGCGUCUGUGAUGAGAGCCACUGCCCUCUGGGGCGGGCUCCUUCUCUGCUAAGCCGUGGGCUUGCACAGGGAAGGGGUCCCCCACCUGGCUAUGCUCAGGUCUCCUCUGCCCAACCUGGCACCUGAGAGACAGCCCAGAUUCUAGAUAUGCUUUGAUACUAAUGCACCAUGCAACCUCCAGCAAGUCAAUUAAUGUAUUGGUUUCCUCAUCUUUAGAGUGGGGUCAGUAACCUCUACCUCCUUGUGGGUUCAGUGGGAGAAAAUCAGUGCAAAGCAUGUGGCCCAGUGCAUGGCAUGGAGUGAGUGCUCAGUUGAUGUGGCGGUGGGGGCCUUUGAUUAUGAGCCAUCCCCUGUGGCCAGGACUCUGCAGGGCUUCCUCAGCAGCCAGGUGCAUGGCCCUGGGCCUCUGGGUGAGGUCUGGAGCAGGCUGGGUGGGCCAGGCACCUCUCCUGUGAAAGCUGGAGGGCUUUGUCCUCAGUCGGUGCCCACUAGUCCCUCCUUAGCCCUGUGGGACCUCCAUACACGGGGUCAGGAAAUGGCAGGCUGGGCGGGCGUAUGGAAGCUUGGGCCUGCUGACUGCUGGGCCUCUGGGAGGGGAGCCAGUGUUUGCUAAGAAUAGUCCCAAAUCAUGGCUUUCGUUUCCCAGAGGGCAGCCCAGCCAUGUGCUGCCCCUGUCUUGGGCCAAGGCACUUGCAGAUGGACUUUUUAUGUUUCCUGUAACUGGUGCUCAGCACAGGAUUGAGCCUGGGAGCAGCAGGCUUAGUCUGGGAGGAGGCUCUGUUUGUCUUCCGAGGCCUUUGGCUGGGACCCGGGGAAAGAGAAGGUCUGGAAGCACUGGCCUUUAUAAUCCCUGAGUUCCUUUUCCACUCAGGGCUUUUCCUGACACAUCUGCCUCGACCAUCUUCCUACCUGCAAAUAGACCUGUUGUGAUUAAGAACACUGGCUCUGGAAAGAAACUACCAGGGUCUGAAUUUCUGCUCCCUCCCUCAUUAGCCAUGUGGCCCAGGGCAAGAAACUUAACCUCUCUGUGCCUCAAGUCCCUUGUGUAACAGGGUUAAGGAUAGCAACUCCCUUAUGAGAAUGUCACAAGGAUGAAAGGAGGUAAUCGCAGAGAGCCUCCGAGGCUGUCUGGCUCCUAGGAAGUACUCAGUAAACAUUAGGUGCUUAUGUUAUUACCACGAUGUUAUUCUCUCAGCAGAGGCCAGGAUGCUUGCACAGGACCAGUUGGUGGGAAGGGACCAGCGUGGCAUCUUGAUGUGGGUUCCUGAGCUUUCUUGGCCCUGGGUUCAGUAUGAGGUGCAGGGGCUCCGAAGGUAGAUUAAACUCUGUCCCUGCCAGGAGGUCUGGGGUCCUGAGGCUGCUGGCAGACUAUGGGUACAACGGCCAGCACAGCCCAGCAGACGGUCUCGGCAGGCACCCCAUUUGAGGGCCUACAGGGCAGUGGCACGAUGGACAGUCGGCACUCCGUCAGCAUCCACUCCUUCCAGAGCACUAGCUUGCAUAACAGCAAGGCCAAGUCCAUCAUCCCCAACAAGGUGGCCCCUGUUGUGAUCACGUACAACUGCAAGGAGGAGUUCCAGAUCCAUGAUGAGCUGCUCAAGGCUCAUUACACGUUGGGCCGGCUCUCGGACAACACCCCUGAGCACUACCUGGUGCAAGGCCGCUACUUCCUGGUGCGGGAUGUCACUGAGAAGAUGGAUGUGCUGGGCACCGUGGGAAGCUGUGGGGCCCCCAACUUCCGGCAGGUGCAGGGUGGGCUCACUGUGUUCGGCAUGGGACAGCCCAGCCUCUCAGGGUUCAGGCGGGUCCUCCAGAAACUCCAGAAGGACGGACAUAGGGAGUGUGUCAUCUUCUGUGUGCGGGAGGAACCUGUGCUUUUCCUGCGUGCAGAUGAGGACUUUGUGUCCUACACACCUCGAGACAAGCAGAACCUUCAUGAGAACCUCCAGGGCCUUGGACCCGGGGUCCGGGUGGAGAGCCUGGAGCUGGCCAUCCGGAAAGAGAUCCACGACUUUGCCCAGCUGAGCGAGAACACAUACCAUGUGUACCAUAACACCGAGGACCUGUGGGGGGAGCCCCAUGCUGUGGCCAUCCAUGGUGAGGACGACUUGCAUGUGACGGAGGAGGUGUACAAGCGGCCCCUCUUCCUGCAGCCCACCUACAGGUACCACCGCCUGCCCCUGCCCGAGCAAGGGAGUCCCCUGGAGGCCCAGUUGGACGCCUUUGUCAGUGUUCUCCGGGAGACCCCCAGCCUGCUGCAGCUCCGUGAUGCCCACGGGCCUCCCCCAGCCCUCGUCUUCAGCUGCCAGAUGGGCGUGGGCAGGACCAACCUGGGCAUGGUCCUGGGCACCCUCAUCCUGCUUCACCGCAGUGGGACCACCUCCCAGCCAGAGGCUGCCCCCACGCAGGCCAAGCCCCUGCCUAUGGAGCAGUUCCAGGUGAUCCAGAGCUUUCUCCGCAUGGUGCCCCAGGGAAGGAGGAUGGUGGAAGAGGUGGACAGAGCCAUCACUGCCUGUGCCGAGUUGCAUGACCUGAAAGAAGUGGUCUUGGAAAACCAGAAGAAGUUAGAAGGUAUCCGACCGGAGAGCCCAGCCCAGGGAAGCGGCAGCCGACACAGCGUCUGGCAGAGGGCGCUGUGGAGCCUGGAGCGAUACUUCUACCUGAUCCUGUUUAACUACUACCUUCAUGAGCAGUACCCGCUGGCCUUUGCCCUCAGUUUCAGCCGCUGGCUGUGUGCCCACCCUGAGCUGUACCGCCUGCCCGUGACGCUGAGCUCAGCAGGCCCUGUGGCUCCGAGGGACCUCAUCGCCAGGGGCUCCCUACGGGAGGACGAUCUGGUCUCCCCGGACGCGCUCAGCACUGUCAGAGAGAUGGAUGUGGCCAACUUCCGGCGGGUGCCCCGCAUGCCCAUCUACGGCACGGCCCAGCCCAGCGCCAAGGCCCUGGGGAGCAUCCUGGCCUACCUGACGGACGCCAAGAGGAGGCUGCGGAAGGUUGUCUGGGUGAGCCUUCGGGAGGAGGCCGUGUUGGAGUGUGACGGGCACACCUACAGCCUGCGGUGGCCUGGGCCCCCUGUGGCUCCUGACCAGCUGGAGACCCUGGAGGCCCAGCUGAAGGCCCAUCUAAGCGAGCCUCCCCCAGGCAAGGAGGGCCCCCUGACCUACAGGUUCCAGACCUGCCUUACCAUGCAGGAGGUCUUCAGCCAGCACCGCAGGGCCUGUCCUGGCCUCACCUACCACCGCAUCCCCAUGCCGGACUUCUGUGCCCCCCGAGAGGAGGACUUUGACCAGCUGCUGGAGGCCCUGCGGGCCGCCCUCUCCAAGGACCCAGGCACUGGCUUCGUGUUCAGCUGCCUCAGCGGCCAGGGCCGUACCACAACUGCGAUGGUGGUGGCUGUCCUGGCCUUCUGGCACAUCCAAGGCUUCCCCGAGGUGGGUGAGGAGGAGCUCGUGAGUGUGCCUGAUGCCAAGUUCACUAAGGGUGAAUUUCAGGUAGUAAUGAAGGUGGUGCAGCUGCUACCCGAUGGGCACCGUGUGAAGAAGGAGGUGGACGCAGCGCUGGACACUGUCAGCGAGACCAUGACGCCCAUGCACUACCACCUGCGGGAGAUCAUCAUCUGCACCUACCGCCAGGCGAAGGCAGCGAAAGAGGCGCAAGAAAUGCGGAGGCUGCAGCUGCGGAGCCUGCAGUACUUGGAGCGCUAUGUCUGCCUGAUUCUCUUCAACGCGUACCUCCACCUGGAGAAGGCCGACUCCUGGCAGAGGCCCUUCAGCACCUGGAUGCAGGAGGUGGCAUCGAAGGCUGGCAUCUACGAGAUCCUUAACGAGCUGGGCUUCCCCGAGCUGGAGAGCGGGGAGGACCAGCCCUUCUCCAGGCUGCGCUACCGGUGGCAGGAGCAGAGCUGCAGCCUCGAGCCCUCUGCCCCCGAGGACUUGCUGUAGGGGGCCUUACUCCCUGUCCCCCCACCCACAGGGCCCCACGCAGGCCUGGGGUGUCUGAGGUGCUCUUGGCUGGGAGCGGCCCUGAGGGGUGCUGGCCUUGAAAUGAUUCCCCCACUUCCUGGAGAGACUGAGCGGAGUUGGGAGCCUUUUUAGAAAGAACUUUUUAUAGGACAGGGAGACAGCACAGCCAUCCCUUGCAAACCACCAAGGUGUGUGGCUGACCUCCAGGGAGGAGCACUCACUGGAGUGCUCACAAGGUGCACACUGCUGUGUGUACCUUGCAGACAGGCCGGCGUUCAGCCUCCAAGGGGCUCACUCCCCCAGUUGCCAAACACUGUGGAUCUCUCUGUCCUCUUCUCCCCUCUCUCAGAUUGGCCUGGCAGCCCCUGGCACAGAGCAGACCCGGCCACUGGUAGCUCCCCACUUCCUUACUCCUGCUGCUCUGCCAUUGCCGCUCCCCUUGUUGCUGCCCAAGCACUGCCCUCGGGCGUCUGGCAGCCUGAGGUGGGUGGAGGGGACAGUGUUCUGGAUAGAUCUAUUAUGUGAAAGGCAGCUUCACCCAGUUUUCUGGACUCUCAUGCCCCCAUCUCCGACCUGGGAGACUUCAGGAAUGACAACCUACCCAGCCUGGUGGGGCUGGCAGGAUGGUGGAGGUUUCUCAAGGAGCUGGAGACUUCAGGGAGCCCCUCUCAUGGGGAGGAAAGAGCUUCCAGGGGGCGAACGCAGCACAGAGGAAGAGGCCUGCUCCACUUGUCUGGGAACCUGGGCAGGAGGCACAGAGGAAGCCAAGGCCUGGAGCUGCAGGUCCCCCGGCAUCUCUCUCUGUCCCGGCAGCCCAGGAUGGCCUGGUGCCCCCACCUGCUGCAGCAGGAGCCCCAAGGAGUGCUAGCUGAGGGUGGUUGCUGGGGUGGUCCUCAUGGACAGUGAGGUGUGCAAGGGUGCACUGAGGGUGGUGGGAGGGGAUCACCUGGGUUCCAGGCCAUCCUUGCUGAGCAUCUUUGAGCCUGCCUUCCGGUGGGAGCAGAAAAGGCCAGACCCUGCUGAGUUAGAGGCUGCUGGGAUCCACUGUUUCCACACAGCGGGAAGGCUGCUGGGAACAGGUGGCAGAGAAGUGCCAUGUUUGCGUUGAGCCUUGCAGCUCUUCCAGCUGGGGACUGGUGCUUGCUGAAACCCAGGAGCUGAACAGUGAGGAGGCUGUCCACCUUGCUUGGCUCACUGGGACCAGGAAAGCCUGUCUUUGGUUAGGCUCGUGUACUUCUGCAGGAAAAAAAAAAAAGGAUGUGUCAUUGGUCAUGAUAUUUGAAAAGGGGAGGAGGCCGAAGUUGUUCCCAUUUAUCCAGUAUUGGAAAAUAUUUGACCCCCUUGGCUGAAUUCUUUUGCAGAACUACUGUGUGUCUGUUCACUACCUUUUCAGGUUUAUUGUUUUUAUUUUUGCAUGAAUUAAGACGUUUUAAUUUCUUUGCAGACAAGGUCUAGAUGCGGAGUCAGAGAUGGGACUGAAUGGGGAGGGAUCCUUUGUGUUCUCAUGGUUGGCUCUGACUUUCAGCUGUGUUGGGACCACUGGCUGAUCACAUCACCUCUCUGCCUCAGUUUCCCCAUCUGUAAAAUGGGAGAAUAAUACUUGCCUACCUACCUCACAGGGGUGUUGUGAGGAUUCAUUUGUGAUUUUUUUUUUUUUUGUACAGAGCUUUUAAGCAUUAAAAACAGCUAAAUGUGA